CUCCAGAAGUUUCCCCCUUGGGCGGUGGUGGAGGUGGUAACCGUGAUAGUAGCAGCUCCGGCGGCAGCAACAGCGACUACGAGGGAUGGCGGCGGCUGCAGCAGGAACUGCAACAUCCCAGAGGUUUUUCCAGAGCUUCUCGGAUGCCCUAAUCGACGAGGACCCCCAGGCGGCGUUAGAGGAGCUGACUAAGGCUUUGGAACAGAAACCAGAUGAUGCACAGUAUUAUUGUCAAAGAGCUUAUUGUCACAUUCUUCUUGGGAAUUACUGUGGGAAAAACUGAAUACCUUGAGUAAAAUUACAUAGAAAAUGUUAAUGAGACAAGGAGGUGAAUUUUGUGACACAGCUGUAUUCAUUGAAGAGCUUUAAGAAGGAAGCUAAAUGUUAAGCCAAAAGGAAGUUGCUGUUGCUGAUGCAAAGAAGUCUCUAGAACUCAAUCCAAAUAAUUCCACUGCUAUGCUGAGAAAAGGAAUAUGUGAAUACCAUGAAAAAAACUAUGCUGCUGCCCUAGAAACUUUUACAGAAGGACAAAAAUUAGAUAGUGCAGAUGCUAAUUUCAGUGUCUGGAUUAAAAGGUGUCAAGAAGCUCAGAAUGGCUCAGAAUCUGAGGUGUGGACUCAUCAGUCAAAAAUCAAGUAUGACUGGUAUCAAACAGAAUCUCAAGUAGUCAUUACACUUAUGAUCAAGAAUGUUCAGAAGAAUGAUGUAAAUGUGGAAUUUUCAGAAAAAGAGUUGUCUGCUUUGGUUAAACUUCCUUCUGGAGAGGAUUACAAUUUGAAACUGGAACUUCUUCAUCCUAUAAUACCAGAACAGAGCACGUUUAAAGUACUUUCAACAAAGAUUGAAAUUAAACUGAAAAAGCCAGAGGCUGUGAGAUGGGAAAAGCUAGAGGGGCAAGGAGAUGUGCCUACGCCAAAACAAUUCGUAGCAGAUGUAAAGAACCUAUAUCCAUCAUCAUCUCCUUAUACAAGAAAUUGGGAUAAAUUGGUUGGUGAGAUCAAAGAAGAAGAAAAGAAUGAAAAGUUGGAGGGAGAUGCAGCUUUAAACAGAUUAUUUCAGCAGAUCUAUUCAGAUGGUUCUGAUGAAGUGAAACGUGCCAUGAACAAAUCCUUUAUGGAGUCGGGUGGUACAGUUUUGAGUACCAACUGGUCUGAUGUAGGUAAAAGGAAAGUUGAAAUCAAUCCUCCUGAUGAUAUGGAAUGGAAAAAGUACUAAAUAAAUUAAUUUGCUCUCAUCGUAUUGUGUAUAUUCACCUAAUGCCCAUUGUGUAUUGAUAUUGCAUUCUUGAAUUUUGAACACUGAAUAUCUUUUUGAAAGAUUAUACUUCUUUACCUCUUUGUGCUUUAGAAAUUAUUUUCCUUCAAGUGUUCAAGUCUAAUGAAGAAUGAAGAUAACAUUUUAUCACUUCUGUCCUUAAAGGUUUCAGACAUGGUGAAACUGAAUAAAGCAUGUCAUUUGCUCCUAGAUAGAUUCAUUCUAUCUAGUUGUGGGGAUGGAGAAAUCUUUAAUGGUAUAUUUUCGGUUAUUGCCUUAUUUUUGAUACAGUAUUCUGUCAGUAAUUUAUUAGACCUGGCAGCUUUGGGUGAGCUUAGAUUUUUCACCUUCAGUGUUACAUUGUGUUUGCUUUUAAAAACUGCUUUUGAAUGGAGUUGUAAAUACAAUUUUUCUAUGAAGAUGUUUGGUUUAUUUACCUUUUUCUUAAGUUUUUAAUGAGAACUUUGAGAAAUUAUCACAGGGAAUUCCCAUGUAGUUCUUUUAAUGGGAAGAAUUUGUAAAUUUAAUUGCACUGAGAUAUUUUGGUCGUUACCUUGCAAGUUUCUGUAUAAAACAUAGAUACCUGAGUUUUAACACACUGCAAGUUUAUACUAAGGAUAAUCUGUGAAGGUAGGGCAAAGAAGGUUCUAGGAAAGCCCAACUCCACUUGCUUCUUUUAUCACGACAGGAUUCUUGAAAUUACAGCAUUGGUGGGUUUUUUGGUAUUUUUUUUCUUUAUUAGAAAAUCUCUGUUGUCACGUCCCCAUGAUUACUUUGGUUUCAUUGGUUUAUGGUAACUGCUGUGAGAGUAAAUUAAUGUGUAUAUGUUUAGUAUUUACUCUGUGCCUAGAAUAUAUAGAUAUCAUGAGAAUACAAAAAAUUAAAGACAUGAUUAUUAACUUCAAAGAGCUUAUAAAUGUAGCAGGGAAAAAAAAUAACAUUCAUGAAGGAACUGUGGAAAGAUUGAAUGCUGAACUCGGUAUAAAUACACUUUAGAGACAGGAAAAUGUUCUGUGAUUAAAAUUGUUUACAGUCUAGGCUGUUAUAAAGUAUAGACUAUGGAUGACCUGUAGAUCUGACUUUGUUUUCUCACCAUGAUUUUCUCAACUGUAAUACCCCAGAUGUUGGUCUCAGCUCUGUUAGGUGUCACUAACAUUUUUAUGGCAAAGCACUACUCUAUACCCUCAGAGCAGGGGGAGUGGGAGGCAAACGGGUCAUCAUUUCAGCCUCCAAAACAGUAGGAAUUCAGCUCCUUCCUUCUCGUCCUUUGUUGUGGGGUGUAGGGGAGUUACUAAGGAAAGUUUCAGUAAGGUGAUACCAGAUGGUGCCCAAACCUGUUGUUAUAGCUUGUUUAAGCAUUCUAGAGUUUUCACUUGUCCUUCUGUCCACUUAGAGCUACUAGAUACAUUUUUUUCUUCUUGAACACUGAAGGAAAAGGCAAAAUUAAGUUUUGGUUGGAUGGAUUUCUAAAGUUUUCUUCUUAGGAAAAUAGGAUAGUGACUUUUGUAUUCUGUAUGUUAAAUUUUCUCAGUACCAUUAAUCCUAAGAUGAAGAGGAAGGCUAUUGCUGCAGAGGCAUAGUUGAGGACGUAUAGCACUAUACCAGAGACAAGAAUGCUUAGCUCUAGCAAGUCUUCUGUCAUUGACUACCUUCAUAAUCUUCAGCAGGUUUAGGCCUUUCUUAGUUCCUUUGUAAAUAAUCCAUAGAGUCUUAGAGUUAUAAUUAAAGGUCCAUGGUUCUAAAUACAGAAGCAUAUUUUUGCCGCUUAACUUUUUCUUUCUUAAAGAUGACACUAUUAAAAUAGCUGUUUCUGACCAGGUGCAGUAGCUCAUGCUUGUAAUCCCAGCAUUUUGGGAGGCGGAGGUGGGCAGAUCACCUGAGGUCAGGAGUUCAAGACCAGCCUGGCCAACAUGGUGAAACCCUGUGUCUACUAAAAAUGCAAAAAUUAGCUGGGUGUAGUGGCAUGCACCUGUAGUCCCAGCUACUUGGGAGGCUCAGGCAGGGAGAAUUGCUUGAACCGGGAGGCAGGGGGUGCAGUGAGCCAAGAUCAUGCCACUGCACUCCAGCCUGGGCGACUCCAUCUCAAAAAAAAUAAAUAGCUGUUUAAAAAAAAAAAAUCUGGUACUAUCUUUAGUUGGUUUUAAAGGAUAUAUUAUCUAGAAUAUGCUUACCCAUUGGCUAGAUUUGCUAAGUGUUGUGGGAUUUGGGAUUUUGCUGGUCUGAAGGGAGUUUGUAAAACACAUGACUGAAAGCAUUAUAAAACAUACCUUGUCAAAUACAUUAGAUUCAUUAUAGGUCAAGGGAAUUUUGAAAAGUAGGCUAGAUUGCUGCCUAAGAAUCCCACUCUAAAGUACUGCUUUGUUUAAUCAUUCUAGAUAAUGGAAGCUUGUAAGCCUCCAGAAAGUUAAAACAAAAAACUUCUUUCUGAUUAAGAGCCUCUUAACUCUAUCCUUAUCCUCUGCUAUCUCAAUGUAGCUAUUAAUUGUUCCCUCUUUGUUUCUAGACUCCAAUUUUCAUUUCUCAAAUUUUGGUUCUCAGUGCUGUUAGUAUUAGUAGCCUUUUGUUUCUUCAGAAUGUAUGUAUUUUUCCUCUUAAAUGUUUCCUUUCCCUUUUAAGGUUAGUCCUGGAAUACAUGUUUUUCUUGGUCUUGUAGACUUCAUCUCUUCUGAUUUCCAUAAUAAUUUGCACCUUGAUGAAUCCAGAAUUCUCCCACUGUCUUCAAAGAAUCUUGAAUAGAAUAAUCUGCUUUUUGAACUCUGCUAUCUAGUAAUCUCUUUAGAUAUCUAUACCACAAGUUUGAAACAUCAAGGUCAAUUUUGAUAAUUUCCUGUCUUAUGUCUUAAUACCCAUUCAGAGUUGACUGCCAACUAACAAGCUCAGCCUUUAGCACUGGCACUUACUGGCCAAUCUGUUUUCUGUCUAUAGGGAGUGAAAUGGAAUGGAGAAAGAGGAUGGCUUGCAUUAAUAACUCUAGUUUUUAAAAACAUUUUUAUUCCUUUUUUAAAAAUUUGUUUAGAGACACGGUCUUCUUCUAUCACCUAGGCUGGAGUGCAGUGGUGCGAUCAUGGCUCACUGUAGCCUCCAACUCCUAGGCUCAAGUAAUCCUCUUUCCUCGGCUUCCCAAAGUGCUGGGAUUACAGGUGUGAGUCACUGUGCCUGGCCCACAUUUUCAUUCUUGGCUCACUGUAGCCUUAAUCUUUCAGGCUCAAAUGAUUCUCCCAUCUCAGCCUCCCAAGUAGCUGGGACCACAGGCAUGCAUCACCACGACUGGCUAAUUUUUGUAUUUUUUUUGUAGAACCGGGUUUCACCAUGUGCCCAGGCUGGUCUUGAACUUCUGGGCUCAAGUUAUCUACCUGCCUCAGCCUACCCAAAGUGCUGGGAUUACAGGAGUGAGCCACCAUGCCCAGUUAUGAACUUCAAGUAAAUAUUUAAAAUGGAGAUACAUCACAAUGCUAUUAUGAAUAAUUUAGAUAGAAAUUUUAAUUUAGUUCAGUACUUAAAUAUUUUUUGGCUCUUCUUUCCCACUUUACCUUUCUCUAUUCCUUCCUCAGUUAUCUACAUAUCAGAUUAGAUUAUUGAUAUCUGAGAUAUAUCACUGACCCAGAGCAAAAUUGCAUAUUAGUUUACCAUCUAAUCAGCCUAAUGCACUUAAAUUCCCUUGGAAUCUUUCCUGUUCAGAUUGGUGUGCAUCUCUCUGAACUUGUAGCUUUACUGACAUUUCCAAAAAAAGGUAGACGGUUUCUAGGUGGUGUGUGUUUUUGUUAGUUACUAGAGCCACUUACCCUUUGUAACUAGCUCUAAAGAAGUACAUCUUUUGCUCAUACCUGCUACUGUAACCAUAUGACAGUAUGGAUUUAAGUUAUUUCUGCCUAGAGGAAUUAGAUGAUAAAAGCUAAAAGGACAAAAUACUGGUUUCUGUGCAGGGAAGGGUCAUAUGUAGUUUUAAAUAAAAGGGUUCAUCUCUUUUGAUGUGGUUUCCCUUUCUCCAUCUGUGCAUUUUUUAAAUCGUAAGAUCAUUUUACACACACCAAGAGAUUUUAUUUUGGGAACUUGUGGGGAAAAUAUUGAUUUACCUACAAAUGUUACUAUUUGGAGCCAUCCUUGUGAUUGGUUUCUGAGAUUAAUUUAACUCUUAGCCUCACUUCCUACCUUAGUAAAGUUGCUCCUCCAAAUCAGCUAAAAUCAUAUACAAUGAAUGCUGACUCAUUACUGCAAAUAGUGGUAGUUACUGUGUACUAGCAUUUCUUAUGGAUUGGGUGGCAUUAUCUCAUUUUUAAUCGCCCUUCAAUAGCAUCCCAUUAUUGCAAAUCAGAAAGAUGAUGGGGCCAAAGUAAAGUUCUUUGCCCAGGUCACUCUACUAGUAAGUAAUUGCAAUAGCUGGGAUUUGAACCCAGGCCUAUCAGACUCCAUUACCCAUACUUCUGACAACUGCAAUCCUCUCAUCAGGUUAAUAAGCUAGAUGUGGAAUGAAUGAUUUUUAUUACCAAAUCAGCUGACUGGAAAUGAAGCAGAGAAUAUUCAAGUUAAAGAACUAAUUCUUUUUUUUUUUUUUUUUGAGACAGUCUCACUCUGUCGUUCAGGGAAGGAAUGCAGUGGUGCAAUCUUGGCUCACUGCAACCUCCACCUCCCAGGUUCAAGUAAUUCUUCUGCCUCAGCCUCCUGAGUAGCUGGGAUUACAGGCAUGGGCCGCCAUGCCCAGCUAAUUUUUGUAUUUUUAGUAGAGACGAGGUUUCACCAUGUUGGUCAGGCUGGUCUUGAACUCCUGACCUCAUGAUCCGCCCACCUUGGCCUCCCAAAAUGCUGGGAUUAUAGGCGUGAGCCACUGUGCCCAGCCAAGAACUAAUUCUUAUAUAGGAGCUGGGAAGAUAAAUUCCUAGAGAUCCUCACUUUCUUAAGUAGGAAAGCUUAUUAGGAAUCCAAAUCUUUUGCCUCAUACUGGAAGUAAUGCAAAGAAGUAGUCUGAUUUUUGAGAGGGUGCUGUUUUUCUCAAAUCUAGAUCAUUACAGAGAAACAGUGUACUUUUAACAACUGUUGCAUGUGUAAGAAGACUGGUACAUGAUGCCAAUGAAAUUCUUUUUUUCCUUUAACUUGGGAGCUCUCAUACCAGUUCCGUUGUACAAAUGCUGAGAUUGUUUCAAGGUUUUAUUCCUACAGACAUGUUAGGAUUUGUGUAUCACUGAUUUCUCCAAUAAAAUUUGAAUAUUUCAGGUUAUUUCCUUUUUCCUAACUUAUGUUAGCAUUUUGUAUAUAUAUAUAUAUUUGAAUUUUGGCUUGUCUGGAGUCUUAAAUAUUUGGUAUGCCUUCACAUUUGGAUUUUUAGUUUUAUUUUUACAUUGAGACUUCUACCUAUAUCAUUGACUUUAUUUUUUCCUAUGAUUAAAGGAUUCAGUUAUACAAAAAGAUGUUUCAGAAACACUGCUAUUUACCUAAAGGUAAUUUUCAGUUUCUUUAGAAGGAGUUAGGAAAAUGGUCCUUAAUACCUAUAUAGGGUUUUUUAAAAAACUGUACCCUAUAAUGCAGCCACAGAAGAUCUAAAUAAUAAACAAUUGCGCAUACUAUUAAUAUAUAUUUAGAGCUUUUGUUAAGUACAUGAAAAGACAGUAUUGCAUAGUGGUUAAAUGCAUGGACUCUGAAGCCAUCCUGUUUGGGAUCAUCCUGGCUACAUUGCUUACUAGCUGUGUGACAAUGGAUAUAGGUGCUUAAUGUCUCUGUGCCUCAGUUUUUGUGUCUAUGUAAAGGAGAUAAUAGGAUCCCCCUCAUGCCUCAUGGUCUUAGUUGAAUGAAUUCAUGUAACUCCACAGGUAUCUUAAUCCAGAAGGCUCAAAAUACUAAUGUUUUGUGUGUGUGUGUGUGUGUGCAUGUGCAUCUGUAUGACAAGUGAUAUAAAACGUGACCUGAAUUUAUAAUAUGAAUAGUCACAUUUUGCAGCAGAAAUAUUAAAUGUUUAAUUAUAGAAUGCUAGCACUGAUCCUGCUGAAAUUGUUACAAAAUACAGCAGUUGCCCCUUAACUGUGGCAGAUACAUUCCAAGACCCCCAGUACUGAAUGCUGUAUGUACAUUUUUUAUACAUGUAUACUUAUGAUAAAGUUUAUAAAUUAGGCACAGUAAGAUAUUAAUAAUAGAAUAUACAAUAUACCGCAAUAAAACUUAUGUGAACAGUUAUUUUUGGACAGCAGUUGACUGUGGGUCACUGAAAUUGUGGAAAGCAAAACCAUGGAUAAAGGGGAACUAUUAAUAGUCUAUCUGUAUUGCAUUAUCUUCUAAAAUCCAAAAUUCUGACUUCAAAAACUCAUCUGAGGGUUUUGGAAUUGUGUAUCUAUGUGUGUGAAGUGCAAAGAGCAGUGCUUCAUGUGACAGAUAACAUCAGAUGAUCCUAGGCUGGAAGGUGGAAAUCCUAGAGAAGAUUUUUUUGUGUUGUAAGUUCAGUCUUUCAAGAUGUGGAAUUCUGUCUGAGGAAAGUAUAUCACCUAGUUAACAAUUGUUACUGUAAUUUAUAAAAUUUGUACUUUGGAGAGCAUAAGAAUUCAUGAAAAGUUUUUAAUAAUUUUACUUAAACAGAGCUUAAUUAUGUAAGUAUUGUCAGCACUUUAUAAAGAAUCGUAAAAUAAAAUAGUGGCAGAAAAUAUAAACUAGAUGUAGAAUGUUAAGGAACUUUCGGAAGUUCUCUGGUUUUCAUUUCAAUUUCAAAGCUCAAAACAGAAGGUAAAACUAUUAGGAUUUGUGAAAAAUACAAGGUACAAAAUCACGCAGUUUAUAAACCACAGAUUGUCUUGUUAUUCCCAUCAGUGAAAAGAAGCUGAUAUUUGUUUGUGUUUGUUUUUGUUUUUGUUUUUGAGACGGAGUCUUGCUCUGUCGCCCAGGCUGGAGUGCAGUGGCGCCAUUUUGGCUCACUGCAAGCUCCGCCUCCCGGUUCACGCCAUUCUCAUGCCUCAGCCUCCCAAGUAGCUGGGACUACAGGCGUCCGCCACCAUGCCCGGCUAAUUUUUUGUAUUUUUAGUAGAGACAAGAGUUUCACCGUGUUAGCCAGGAUGGUCUCAUCUCCUGAUCUUGUGACCCGCCCGCCUCGGCCUCCCAAAGUGCUGGGAUUACAGGCGUGAGCCACCAUGCCCAGCCUGCUGGUAGAUGUUUUUAUGAGUUAAUUCAUCAAUCUUAUUAUUCUUGCCCCAAAUGAAUCAGUGUGGAGCAUAUACAAGUGUGUAGACAUUAAUAUGGGCUCACUGUCAGCUGGGAGUUCUCACAACUACCACUUUUUACUGAUUAUCUGUUUUCUAAACUUUUUCUGUGGCUUGAAGUGACUGAAAGUGAACACAUUCAUAAGUAAUGAGCUUAGGCUGAGGAUAUAUAUCCAGUGGGGGAUGAAACAUGCUUAAGAAAUUGAGUGCAUUUCCUUUAUUAUUGUUAUUAUUUUGCUAUUUCAAAACAAUUGACUUUAAAAAAUUAUACUUCACCACAGAGACAGGUGUUGUUUUGUAAUGGAAGGAGUAGUAACUUAUGAAUCUAGACUCUUAAAAUCCCAGUUCUGAUACUUUCAUAAUUGUGUGUUUUGAGGGCAAGUGACUUAUCUGAACUUUUUUCUUUUUUAUAACACUGGAUGAUAAUUAACCCUCAGGAUUGUGAGGAUUUAAUAACUAAGUCCUGACUCAAAUUAUGUUACCAAUAAAUGCUACUUAAAUGUAAAGUCCUUGAUUUAUUUUUUCCCCUCAGUCCUGUUUAGUGUUGAAAUUCUUCAAAGGAGGGUGAGUCUGGCAUUUACCUGCUAUUCAAGAGUUUUCAGAAUUCAACCCCAGCCAAAAUUUUUGGCCACAUCUCUUGUCACUGCUUUGCUGUGUACUAAAGCUCCCAGACACACAAGAAUCUUCUAGUCAUGGUCAAACUUUUUCUGCAAAGGGCACUUACAGUCUAUUGCAUAUUCUUUGUUUUUAGUGUUCAGACAUCUGCUGUUUCUGAAUAUGUCGUGUAUUUUCAUUCCUUUUUCUGCCCCUCCUGGGCAUCUCCAGUUUCCUACUGAUGUGUCAAAACUGAGUUUGUAUGCUACCUCCAGGAAAGCAGUCUAAUCUUUUGCAACUCUGUUACUGACUUUUGUGGCAUUGGAUUGGGUUAUUUGCUUAUGGUUGAGACAUCACUGGAUCCUUUGAUGGAGUCAUACCAAAACCACAACAUGUCAUGAGCAUGCUUGAGAGUGCUAAUCUAUUCCUUGUUUGUCAGACCAGUACAUUACAGUUGGUUCAUUUCUUCCCCCGUGUGACUGAGUUUCUUGAGGGCGCGGUCUAGCUUCCAUCUUUGUAUGUGUAGCACCUGGUACAUAGAGAACAGGCUCCCAGAAUUGGAUGGAUUUGCUCAUGGUCUUAUCACUGCACAGAAUGCCCUUAUUUUCUUCCAUUCAUUCUAUGAGAUCUCAAUUAAAAUGUCAGUACUCUUGUGGAACUCCCCUCUCCAUGCCCUCUACUGAAAUGCAUUGCCACUCUAGUUGUGAUGUGGGAGUGCCUUGUUUAUGCCUCUAUUUAUGACACCUUCAUGGUGUCACAUGUUAUAGGGUUAGUUGCGGCUGUGUCUGUUUUACCUUGUGUGUCUUGGUCAGUUAGUGUUAUUUACUUAAGCUUUGGAUCUUUGAUACAUAGCGUAGUGCCUUUCACAUAGUAUGUACUCAAAUAUUGGAAGUUACUCAUCCCAAACCAUAGUGUUUAAAAUUGGGGUUUUUUAAAAAUGUCAAGCCCUUAAAGUUGAUCAUUUAUUUGUCAAUGUAAAUAGAAUAGUAAUUUGUUUUCAAAAAGAUGAGGUCUUGCUGUGGUGCUCAGGCUGGAGUGCAGUGGCUGUUCACAGGCGUGAUAAUUGUGUGUUACAGCCUCAAAGUCCAGGGCUCGAGUGAUCUUCUCACUUCAGCCUCCUGAGUAGCUGAGACUAGGCGUGCACCACCGUUUCUGACAGGAUUUUAAUUUUUAAGUAGGUUUUUAACCCACAGCCACGAGAGCUAAUUUUAACUACAUUGUUAGAGGUAGUAACAGUUAUAUAACUAAUCAAAACCAGUGUGAUAUCCAAGUACUUUUUUUUUUUUUUUUUUUUGCUAUUUAAUUUUGAGAUACCAUUUUUUGGAGGGGUGUCCUGAUUUAUUUUAUUUAUUUUAUUUAUUUAUUUUUAUUUUUUAUUUUUUUAGAUAAGGUCUUGCUCUUGCCCAGGCUGGAAUGUAAUGGCAUGGUCGCAGCUCACUGCAGCCUCCGUCUUCUGGGCUCAAGCAAUCCUCCUUCCUCAGCCUCCUGAGUAGCUGGGACUACAGGUGUGUGCCACCACUCCCAGCUAAUUUUUAAAUUUUGUGUAGAGAUGGGGUCUCCCUGCAUUGCCCAGGUUGGUCUCUCAAACUCCUGGGUUCAAGCAGUCCUCCCACCUUGGCCUCCCAAAGUGUUGGGAUUAUAGGCGUAAGCCACUGUGCCCGGCUGUUUUUUGUUUUGUUUUGUUUUGUGUUUUAAUUGAACGGACUGAAGUUUACUUUCUAACUAGGUUAGCCCUCCAUUCAUACAAAAUUAUGAGCCCAAAUGUCUUGGGGAGAGUACAGGAGAGGCCAGAUCUUAAAAGCCAGGAGUGGAAUUAGGUUUGAGCAUAUGUAGCAAUAUGGAAACAAAGAGUGAGUCAAUUUAUAAGCAUACCAAUCUUCUUGGAGACAAAAGUUUGAAUUGCUCACGUGUCCAUUUUUUUUCUGGAAUCCCUGAAGAAAUUUUGAGAUACUGAGUACUAGAAAACCCUCUUUGAUGAGGGUUGUAUACUUUAUUUUUAAACAGUAUCAACACCGUUGAGGCCCUUCAAGUCUUUGCAGUCAAAAGCCAUACACUUUUUCUUUGAGUGAGCCUUUACUUUAAGGUAUGUAGUAGAAUAAUAUAGGUAUCUGAAAAAGAACUUGGUUCAUGACAUCCACUCAUUCAUUUAUGCACUUAGCAAAUAUUCAUUGAUUGCCAAAUACGCAUCAGACACUGAGCUAGGUGCUAGGUACUAGGUAAACAAAAUUCCCUGCCUUCAUGGAGCUUAGCUUGUGGUGGUGGAAAGAAGCCCUCAGCCUGAAUACUCAACUUAUGUCUGCCGUUUAUUCCUUAACACAUUAAACUAUAGGUAAUAGCAUAUGUUAGUCUAAUCUUUGUUUAGCAAAGCUAUUUCUUGUUCUGGAAUAUAAGUACAGUUACAGCAGAAUAAGUACCAAGGCAAGAUUGGAGAAUGACCGGUUGUGAACAGGGACUUAGGAAUAUGUGUAGCAUAGGAUUUUAUUUUAGAGUUGUUAAAAUCAGAUCAACAGAGCAUGUUUUUAUGGGCCAUCUGACAAGACUAGAGGUAGCUUUGGAACCUCUUAUUCCCUGGAAUGCAAACAUGUAUUUGCAUUUCAUCCACUGUCAGUAUGAGGAGACAAAAACGAAGUCAGGAUUUUGGAGCUGGAAUGGAUCUUAAAUACUAUGUAGUCCAAACGUUUGGUUUUACAGAUGCACUUUUUCCAGAGUGCUGUCAUCUCAUAUACUUUUUUCUUCAUACAGGUUUUUAAUGUAACUCACUCAGAUCGUUGGUGAUAGACUCUCUCUUAAAACUUAUUUAUCCUAAUCUUUUUUUUUUUUUUUUUUUUAAGAGACAGGGUUUUGCUCUGCUGUCCAGGCACACAAUAGCUCACUGUAACCUCCAACUCCUGGAGUCAAGUGAUCCUCCUGCCUCAGCCUCUCAGGUAGCUGGGACUGCACUACUAGUGCACUAAGCUAAUUUUUAAAUUUUUUUUGUAGAGACAGGGUCUUGCUGUGUUGCCCGGGCUGCUCUCUUAACUCCUGGCCUCAAGUAAUCCUCUUGCCUUGGCUUCCCAAAGUGCUGGGAUUACAGGCGUGAGCCACCAUGCUUAGCUGAUUUGCCCUAAUCCUCUGCUGACAUUCUGAUAUCGGACAACUAAAAUUAUAACAUUGGGCAGCUAUUUUGUAUGAUAUAUAGGGUAGUGGUUCUUAAGCUUAUUGGUGAGUAACCUUCACUUGGGAAGCUUAUUUUUAAAAAUGUAGACCUUCAUUACUUUCCUCCUGAGAUUUUGAAUCAGUACCUUUGAGAGAGGGUCCAGUAAAUCUUUGUUUUGAAUGAACUGAUGGUUUUGAAGCAGGUGACCUGGAGGACUGCAUGUAGAACACAGUGAUGUCAAGGAGUAAAGGAGAGAACAGAAGUGAGAUUAGCACUAAUCACCUCUAAUGCCUUAUUUCCAGUAAAGUUUAGAGAAGAGGAAAAGCUACUUGGCUUGCUCCUUUGAAGGUUUUGUUUCCCUCUUAACACAGAAAUUAAAAGGUAGAGGAGAGAUGCUGAAUGAUGCUUUUUUUCUUCUUAAUCUUGGGGGGUCAUUAUGAUUAAGUUAUUGAAUCCAUAUCACCGUAUGACAGCACAUGAUGAAAGAAAAUCAAAUGUUUGUUUCAAUCAAAGUGAAACAAAAUGAGAAUAACUAUUUGGGCAAAACACUUUUAUCACUGCUAAGAUAUUACUAGAACUGAGCAGAGAAAUACUCAGAGAGAGCCAUGGCAUAGUACUAAUUAAUAAUGGGGUACCAUUUAGCAACUGGAAUAUUCUCCGAUGAUGCCUGUUUAAUUACCCAUAGGUGCUAAGUGAAUGUUAAAAAUUACGGUGCUGGUUGAGUAGGCCGAGUAGAAUUUGUGUUAGGGCACAUCCCAUGGAGAUCUUUUUUACUGCUUAAUUUUUUGGAGUUACCUCAGUAACUUAACAGGCAGGAAUAUGGUUUUAAUGGAAAGGAAACCAUUUGCCUUUAACAGCAUUAGUCCCGCUAAGAGAAAGUUUUUGCUUGUCUAGUUUAUUACAGGUCUUUGACUUUGUCAGUAUAUGGCAAAUUUAGUAUAAAAGAUGAUUAAUUAUCAAGGCUGAUGAAAUAUAGGCAGCUGAAAAGAAAAUUCUUAGCAAUUCAUACCUUAGAAGGAACCCUGAAGGACAGGACGCCAUAGAAAUCCUGUUUUUUUAAAAAAGUAAUUUCAAGUAAGUUUGCAAAUGCAAUGCUAGUAAAAAGUAUAUAGAGGUAUGUCUUUCACACUAUCUUGUUACUAUUAGAAUUUUUGUAGCCAUGUGCAGAGGAGAGAAAAGGUGUUGGAUUUUCUGCAGUUCUGAUUCAGUUCUAAGAAUUUGGUGUGAAAAGAAUGUUUGCAAAGGAGCAGGCACAAAGGUGAGAACAGGAAUACGAAACACAACAUCUGUAAAUGACUAAAUUCAGAGGGAAUUUAGUGGGGCAUAUCUCUUAAAUGGUUUUGAAUAAUUUGGUGUUUUAACCAAUGACUUAAUUUAACUUAGUGGGUAUACUGUUCCCAGUCCCAUUACUGAUUUUUAUUCCUCUGUGAUAACAUACACCCAAAUAAAGACUGCUAUGUAUUUGACUUUAAAACUAUAAAGAUGUAAAAAAGGUUCACUAAGCCAAACACCUUAGAAAAUAGCCUCAGCUAUUUGCUAUGUUUAUAUUAUACCUGCAUAAAAGUAUUUAUGUAUAGAUGUACUUACCUUACACAGUAAGUACCUAAAAUUUGUAAAUUGAAUACUUUUGAAUGUAAGCAGUUGAAGUAAAACCUGUAGUGAGUUCUUCAGUCAGUCAACACUAAACCUGUUUUGUAAAUUUGAUGCUAGUAUUAUACUGGACUUUCUCAAAAUGAAGUACACCUAUAUAUGCAUAUAGUAUAUGAGCAUGUGUAUUUGUACAAAAGCCCUUCAAAAGGAGUUCAGCUUUUAUAAACACCAAAACACUCUCUGCCUGUAAAAUGUUUUUGCUGAAAUUUGUAUCAUUAACUCUCAAAUUUACAUCUUCAUGUUUGAGAUACGCUUUUAGGACUGUCUAUGCAUGUAGACUUUGGUCAACUCUCUCCUCCUCCCUCAAUAAAUCAGUUAACUUAAAAAAUAUAUUGUGACCAUUUUUAUAAAAUACAUGUUCAUAAAACAGAUCAACAUAUUUAGCUUAUACAGAAAUAAAAUUAAGUCAAUCCACUCACAAAGAAUUUCUAUUUUGUAAAAAUGUAGCUUGUAUUUCAGUAUAAUAAAAUCUGAUGUAAGAAA